CUCUUGUUCCUCCUCCUGCCUCUCUUCGCUUCGCCUGCAAACGCGGUGGGGGCUGCUCGGCGGUCAGGAGCAGGUUACCCUCCGUCUGCAUGCCCACCAUCAAGGUAUGAGGAUGGUAGAAGCUCUCGUCGAACCAGAUGGAUGAAGACCACUAACGGCUUUUGUUUCCUCUGGUAACAGCAAGAGACAGAGCGACAUGAGAGAUUGGACCGCGGGCUGCACUGGAGAAUUUACUGGUAGGAUAAUUCAUCCCUAAAGAGAUUGAAGUGAGCUUCAGAAUGGCAAAAGAGGAGCCCCAGAGUAUCUCAAGGGACUUGCAGGAACUGCAGAAGAAGCUGUCUCUGCUGAUAGACUCCUUCCAGAAUAACUCAAAGGUGGUGGCCUUUAUGAAGUCUCCAGUGGGUCAGUACUUGGACAGCCAUCCGUUUCUGGCCUUCACCUUGCUGGUGUUCAUUGUCAUGUCGGCCGUUCCUGUUGGAUUCUUCCUGCUCAUCGUGGUGCUUACCACCCUGGCUGCUCUGCUGGGGGUCAUAAUAUUGGAAGGAUUGGUCAUCUCUGUGGGUGGCUUCUCACUGCUCUGCAUCCUCUGUGGUUUGGGCUUCGUAUCACUCGCCAUGUCGGGGAUGAUGAUAGCAUCUUAUGUAGUGGUCUCCAGCCUCAUCAGCUGCUGGUUUUCUCCCAGUUGUCAGCCGGCUUCUCGUUUGUGUGGCUGCAUUCAUUCUGUUGUGCUAUGUUGUCCUGUUUGGAGUAUUUGAAGAAGACCUAGCAUCACUAACAUGCGGUUGGGAGAGGGAGGCAAAGCUUUUUUAAACGAUUGUGGAUAUUCUAUGAUAGUCCACCAAAACUCCGUAAGUGAUAGUUUCUUAAAGGUUAGCUGAAAUGUGAAAUUUUUCUACUCUAUUUUAUUGAAAUCUUCAGGUCUGUGUCACACUUUAAAUUGAUCUUUAUCAUGCAUGAUUUUCUAACUUUACCCAUUGGUCAAUGGGAGAAUAUCAAUUCAUUGAGUCAUGCAGAUCUUCCAAAUAUAUUUUGAAAAAUUGCACUGUUCCCUUGUGAGAGAAUGUGAGUGAAAAAGGCAUAUAAUAGGUCAUGUUAUUGUGAACAUGGUUUUCAUCUGAGAACCCUUGCAUUAGCGAAUUCUUUUUUUUUUUUUUUUUUUUGAGACGAGUCUCACUCUCACCCAGGCUGGAGUGCAGUGGCUUGAUCUUGGUUCACACAACCUCUCCCUUCUGGGUUCAAGCAGUUCUUCUGUCUCAGCCUCCCGAGUAGCUGGGAUUAUAGGUGUGCACCACCAUGCAUGGCUAAUUUUUGUGUUUUUAGUAGAGGUGGGGUUUCACCAUGUUGGCCAGGCUGGUCUUGAACUCCUGAGCUCAAGUGAUCCACCCACCUCAGCCUCCCAAGAUGCUGGGAUUAUAGGUGUAAGCCACUGUACCCAGCCUGCAUUAGUGAAUUCUUUAUAACUCAAAAAAAGAUAACUCCCUCAUUAAAUGAUCGAAAGCAUGGAAUGGGGGGAAGAGGAGCUAUAUAAUUUAUUUCAUGAUUUAAUGGAAUUUUGGCCCUAAAACAUAAAAGAUAAUACAGCUUAAAUUUUUAAAAAAGAAAAGAAAAAGGAAACAAAACUGUAAGUUUCCCUUACAUAUGAAACCCAACUAAACAAUAUUUAGAUCAAAUACACUGACCUGCCUCCUAUGUAGAUCAGCUAGCCUCUGAGGGGCAAAACCACACUGCUUGGUUAUGGAGACUGCAAGACCUUCCAGGGCCUGCAGCUCAGGAGAAGUAGGGGCCCUGGGCAGCUGUGUUUAUUUGCAGAGCCACCAAACUCACUACCCCAUAUCAUAAUCUUCCAAACCAGCCUGAGCAUAACUAGCUUCCUUACAUCUUUACUAAGAAAAGGAAAGGCUUCUUUCUUAGUUUUUUGUUAUCAGGGAGGAAUGGUUUAGGUGGCAAAUAAUGAAAAAAACCAAAGUAGAUACUAGUUUAAACACACAGGGAACUUUUUUUUAUUGCUUAAUGAAAAACUGGAGACAGCCCAGGGCUGGUGCAGCCAGUGUGGUAUCAACAUACCAGGCACCUUUUGCCUUCCUGUGUUGCUAUCCUUAGCCCAUUGGUUUCCUACCUUAUGGCCACAAGAUAGCUGCUGCAGCUCCAGAUCUACCAGCUACCUUCAAGGCAGCAGAAAAGGAGAAAAAAAUGGAGUCUGACCCUUUUAAAAAUGUGAAUAAAAUAUUUCCCAGGACCUCUCACCACUAUACUUCAAAAGACUUCAUUGACUAGAACUUUGUCAGAUGGCCGCUGGUUGCUGUUCUCCUGAUUGUAGGUCUCACGAGAUCUGAUGGUUUUAUAAAGGGCAUUUCCCCUGCACAUGCUCUCUUGCCUGCCGCCAUGUAAGAAGUGCCUCUGAUCUUCCUUUGCCUUCCACCAUGAUUGUGAGGCCUCCCCAGCCAUGUGGAAUU